AUAUUUUUCCCAGACGCGGAGGUUGGGGUCAUGGCGCCCCGAAGCCUCCUCCUGCUGCUCUCAGGGGCCCUGGCCCUGACCGAUACUUGGGCGGGCUCCCACUCCUUGAGGUAUUUCAGCACCGCUGUGUCGCGGCCCGGCCGCGGGGAGCCCCGCUACAUCGCCGUGGAGUACGUAGACGACACGCAAUUCCUGCGGUUCGACAGCGACGCCGCGAUUCCGAGGAUGGAGCCGCGGGAGCCGUGGGUGGAGCAAGAGGGGCCGCAGUAUUGGGAGUGGACCACAGGGUACGCCAAGGCCAACGCACAGACUGACCGAGUGGCCCUGAGGAACCUGCUCCGCCGCUACAACCAGAGCGAGGCUGGGUCUCACACCCUCCAGGGAAUGAAUGGCUGCGACAUGGGGCCCGACGGACGCCUCCUCCGCGGGUAUCACCAGCACGCGUACGACGGCAAGGAUUACAUCUCCCUGAACGAGGACCUGCGCUCCUGGACCGCGGCGGACACCGUGGCUCAGAUCACCCAGCGCUUCUAUGAGGCAGAGGAAUAUGCAGAGGAGUUCAGGACCUACCUGGAGGGCGAGUGCCUGGAGUUGCUCCGCAGAUACUUGGAGAAUGGGAAGGAGACGCUACAGCGCGCAGAUCCUCCAAAGGCACACGUUGCCCACCACCCCAUCUCUGACCAUGAGGCCACCCUGAGGUGCUGGGCCCUGGGCUUCUACCCUGCGGAGAUCACGCUGACCUGGCAGCGGGAUGGGGAGGAACAGACCCAGGACACAGAGCUUGUGGAGACCAGGCCUGCAGGGGAUGGAACCUUCCAGAAGUGGGCCGCUGUGGUGGUGCCUCCUGGAGAGGAACAGAGAUACACAUGCCAUGUGCAGCACGAGGGGCUGCCCCAGCCCCUCAUCCUGAGAUGGGAGCAGUCUCCCCAGCCCACCAUCCCCAUCGUGGGCAUCGUUGCUGGCCUUGUUGUCCUUGGAGCUGUGGUCACUGGAGCUGUGGUCGCUGCUGUGAUGUGGAGGAAGAAGAGCUCAGAUAGAAACAGAGGGAGCUACUCUCAGGCUGCAGCCUACUCAGUGGUCAGCGGAAACUUGAUGAUAACAUGGUGGUCAAGCUUAUUUCUCCUGGGGGUGCUCUUCCAAGGAUAUUUGGGCUGCCUCCGGAGUCACAGUGUCUUGGGCCGCCGGAAGGCCCAGCUCCUGAGUGUCUCUACCUCUCAAACAAGUAUUCUCAUCCAGGAGCAAUUUUCCCACCAGAGGACAUUAGCUAUGUCUGGAAAAAUGUUUUGUUGCCAUGACUGGAGUGAGGAGGAGGUGCUACCAGCAUCUUGUGGGGAAUGACCAGGGAUGCUGAACAUCCUGCAGUGCACAAGUCAGCCCAAUCACCCACAUAACAGAUAAUUAUCCAGCCCCAAUACCAAGAUUGCCAAGGGUAAGGAGGCCUGCCAGGACUUUCUCUCCCUUGAGUACAAGCUUCCUUGAACUGAGGGACACCCUGAAGGAAAAGUGUGGUCCCACCCCAGUCAUCUCUCCCUUCCCUGGAGCUCCAUCUGUAUGCCUGUAGUGCUUAGGCCUGUAACCUGGGGUCCAGGAACCCACCUUCCCAUGAGACUGCAUGCAGAAGUGAUGAUAUGUGCACACAUGACUUCAUUACAGGGCAUUGGAUGUUGAUAUUCAUCAGGUCAGCUGGGGCCCAAGACACUACUCUUCUGCCAACAGGCCGCAAUCCUCUGCAUUAGAGAGAGGGUAAAGAUUGAGGGAGGCCCUAACUUCAAACCUUCUAUCACUGCUAGUGAAGUGCCAAAAAGAAGUGCAAGGUCAUCUGCCCUUGUAGGAACCACACAGGAAGGCAGAGUGUCCACCAAUGUCAAAUUCCAUCAAAGAAAUAAUAUUUUGACAAAAAAUGCAAGUCACCUUUCUAAGUCCCAGACAGCAGCUCAAAAUAAAAAGCAUUAAACCCCUCAAAUCUUAGACCAGGUGAAAUUAUUGAAGCUGCAGUAAGGUCUUGUGGGACCUGCAGUUAGAGAGAAGGGACAACUCAAUUUGGGACUGCAGCAGAAACCCCUACAUCAUGGGGUUCCUGGAAGGGACCCUCUCCCUUCAGCGACGCAUUGUGAGGCCAUUUCUAGGUAAAAAGGUAGAAUUUCCUUGGAUUCCUGAGGUUUAUUUUACACUUACUGCUUAUUCUUUGACUUUAUAGAAGCCAACUUCAGUUUGAACAUCUUGCAAUUAAUUUUUUUUGGCUCUAAGUGGAGAAUUUGAACUUGUUUCUGAAGAAAACCAGGGGCUCCUUAUGUGAGCAAGCAACCCUCCCUGUGGCCCCCUUAUGCAAUAAACAUAAGCCAUUGUGAGCCAGCAAAAUUUAAAGCAAGGAAAGCAGUAAACCCUCCAUUUCAGCAUGUUUCAGCCUGUCUAGUGAUGUUCUAGUCUUGCCUCACUCUUAACAUUUUAAAAUUUAUAAUUUUAUUUGAUUUUGAUUUAAUAAGAAUUCAUAUGUAUUCAUUUCUUUUGGGUUUGUCACCAAAAGCCUCCUCCAAUCACCUGUGGAGUAAAGACAAGUAAAUAAAUGCAUGGUGUUCCCAUUUA